GAGGACCCACUGGGACCCAAUGGCCUGCAUGUGAAGCCAGGCCUUGGGCCACCUCGUUCCUCAAAGGGGUGCUGACUUCCAUGGGGUGUUCAAAGGGACUGUGGAAAGAGAGGCCUUCAGCCCACACCUCUGAAUGCUUUUCGACCACAGCAUGCCCUGUGGCCUUUAUCCUGCUGGUGUGGAACAGUCAGAGCCCUGCAGGGCUGCAGAGCUUCUGUACUGGGCGGCAUCCCAGCCUGAGUGUCAGAGCUCAGAGAGCAGGCACCGGAGCAAGUAGAGAGGAGGGCACCUUUUGGACAGAAUGUGUGGGACAAGAGCGACGGCUCAUCCAUUCAGGUUCCUCAGAAAAUGAGAGUCAGGAAGAUGAGGGCGCAGACCUGAUUCCCUACACAGGGCUGAAAGCAGACAACCGGAGGAAGAGCAGCACCUGGGCCAACGAGGUAGAAGACAGAAGACCACAGUCUACUCCUGCCCUCAAUCUCACCCCUUCCCACCCACAUCCUCCACGCCCCCUGAUCACCUUCCUCAGAAGUGUAAUAGGAAUCCAGAUUCCCCCUGGCCUGGUUGCUGCGGGAGGCACAGUGGCCUGAUGGAGCCUGAGGCAGGUGUGGGAAGAUGUGGAUUGUCUAACUGGAGGUUGGGAGUUCAGGGUGAGGAAGGAGAAGCUUGGAGUGCAGG